CUUGUGGCUUUGUCUCCCGCGAAGAGGAGAUGGCGGAGUCGUUGAGGUCUCCGCGCCGCUCCCUGUACAAACUGGUGGGCUCGCCGCCUUGGAAAGAGGCUUUCCGGCAGAGAUGCCUGGAGAGAAUGAGAAACAGCCGGGACAGGCUCCUAAACAGGUACCGCCAGGCUGGAAGCAGUGGGCCAGGGAAUUCUCAGAACAGCUUUCUAGUUCAAGAGGUGAUGGAAGAAGAGUGGAAUGCUUUGCAGUCAGUGGAGAAUUGUCCAGAAGACUUGGCUCAGCUGGAGGAGCUGAUAGACAUGGCUGUGCUGGAGGAAAUUCAACAGGAGCUGAUCAACCAAGAGCAGUCCAUCAUCAGCGAGUAUGAGAAGAGCUUGCAGUUUGAUGAAAAGUGUCUCAGCAUCAUGCUGGCUGAGUGGGAGGCAAACCCACUCAUCUGUCCUGUAUGUACAAAGUACAACCUGAGAAUCACAAGCGGUGUGGUGGUGUGUCAGUGUGGCCUGUCCAUCCCAUCUCAUUCUUCUGAGUUGACAGAGCAGAAGCUUCGUGCCUGUUUAGAGGGUAGUAUAAAUGAGCACAGUGCACAUUGUCCCCACACACCUGAAUUUUCAGUCACUGGAGGAACAGAAGAAAAGUCCAGUCUUCUCAUGAGCUGUCUGGUAAGCGUCUCCUGGGACCCACUCUGUGGUAAGAGGGACCUGUGGUUGGUUUUAUUCCCACCUUGAUAGAAAUAAUGACCUAUAAACAGGUAAAUGUUUAAUGCAGUUUAUUAUCUGAGGAAUUUACCUGCAUAGAAAAGUGAAGGUAACAAGUCAUUUAGACUCAAAGGCCAGUCAGAAAGAAGGGAAGAGGCAGCAUGGGAUCACGGCAAGAGGAUUGGUCUGGGAGUUAGGACGCCUGGCUCCACACCUGCUCUUCUUUGAUCAGUAGUAGUGGUUUUGGAUUCAGCUGGUCAUUUCAUAGUCAUAAGACCCAGAUAGGCCAUGCUGGCACCACUUUUGCGGAAGGAAACAGGGCAGAAGCAUAGCAGGGCAGCAUUAGGUUUGUCUGUCAGUGGAGUUUUUACAGAGGUCCAAGGGCUAUUCGCUAACCUGAGUGACAACUGAGGUGUGAGGGCCAGGAACACAAGUGGGUAAGGGAACCACCUGUCUUAGAAGCGUGCUAUAGGAACCAAUAUCUCUUAUAAUCCAUGUCCUUUCCAUAUAUGUGUAUGUAUGUAUGUACAUGUGUAUAUAUAUCACACAAACACACAUAAAACCAAUAUGAUACGUAUUAUUAUUGCUUUUAGAUCCCAGGCAGGGGGAGCCUUGGGAUUAGGAGCACACUGUACUUCAGGAAGUUCAUAGCCAUGGCUUUCUACUGGGAAUUUAGAAUUCCUUCAUGGCCCUGUCAUUCCAAAUGCAGUUAACCUACAGAGGUCAUUUUUAUUAUAAGCAGCAUUGCCUGGUAACAGCCAUUUCACCUUUAUCAAGUUUCUUCCAUAGGUAUUCUACUCAUUCAUUAAAAAAAAAAUGAAUUGAGGACUCAUUAACAUUGAGAAAUACACAUCUCUCACAGAGCUCAAGCCUUGGGUUGGUAAUAAGAGAACAGAAUAAACAGGCAGUACCCUGGAGAGCUGUACAAGGAGGGCUUAUGGGAGUUCAGAGGAGGGUGAUCUCCUUUAUGGUGACACCUUCCUGGAGGAGGCAUUUAACUUGGCCUUGAAGCAUGGAAUCGAUCUGGACAGACAUGGAGAUCUGGUGAGUUGUGGGGGUAGAGCUUAAGUGGAAGAUCCCCACAUAGAAGAACAAGGCAGAGAAGCAGGAAACUGGAGUAUAUACAAAGAGCAUCUUGUUCUACUUAGCUGGAGCAUUAGGUUCAUGAGGGAGAGGAUAGUUCCUGUUAGGAAUAGGAAACAGAUUCAGAGAAGUGAUGUAAUCUGGCCAAAAUUUUACUACUAAUAAGCGAUAGAGCUGGUGUUAGACCCCAGGUCUUUGUGGUUCCAGUGCCCCUGCUGUUUCCUGCUCCAGGCUCAGGCCUUGGUGGAAGGAUGCCAUUUUCCAUCAGCUUGUAUGGAAAGAGACAUAGCAGGUGAAAGUUUAAAUAAAACCCCUCACUACUUCCUGUUGA